AUUACUCGCCAUUUCAAAAUGCUGCCGAGGCCCUAGGAUCUGUGACUGCCACCCCUCCCCCCACCCGGGCUCGGCGGGGGAGCGACUCAUGGAGCUGCCGUAAGGUGUGGCUCUUGGCCUUCGUCGGCGGGGUGCCGGGAGCGGGAGCUGGAGAGUGAGGAGCAGGCGGCCGUACCGCCAGUUGUGCGGGUAGCGGGCGGGAGGAGCUUGAGAGUUUUACCAACAGACUGCAGUUUCUUCACUACCAAAAUGACAUCAUUUUCCACCUCUGCUCAGUGUUCAACAUCUGACAGUGCUUGCAGGAUCUCUCCUGGACAAAUCAAUCAGGUACGACCAAAACUGCCGCUUUUGAAGAUUUUGCAUGCAGCAGGUGCGCAAGGUGAAAUGUUCACUGUUAAAGAGGUCAUGCACUAUUUAGGUCAGUACAUAAUGGUGAAGCAACUUUAUGAUCAGCAGGAGCAGCAUAUGGUAUAUUGUGGUGGAGAUCUUUUGGGAGAACUACUGGGACGUCAGAGCUUCUCCGUGAAAGACCCAAGCCCUCUCUAUGAUAUGCUAAGAAAGAAUCUUGUCACUUUAGCCACUGCUACUACAGAUGCUGCUCAGACUCUCGCUCUCGCACAGGAUCACAGUAUGGAUAUUCCAAGUCAAGACCAACUGAAGCAAAGUGCAGAGGAAAGUUCCACUUCCAGAAAAAGAACUACAGAAGACGAUAUCCCCACACUGCCUACCUCAGAGCAUAAAUGCAUACAUUCUAGAGAAGAUGAAGACUUAAUUGAAAAUUUAGCCCAAGAUGAAACAUCUAGGCUGGACCUUGGAUUUGAGGAGUGGGAUGUAGCUGGCCUGCCUUGGUGGUUUUUAGGAAACUUGAGAAGCAACUAUACACCUAGAAGUAAUGGCUCAACUGAUUUACAGACAAAUCAGGAUGUGGGUACUGCCAUUGUUUCAGAUACUACAGAUGACUUGUGGUUUUUGAAUGAGUCAGUAUCAGAGCAGUUAGGUGUUGGAAUAAAAGUUGAAGCUGCUGAUACUGAACAAACAAGUGAAGAAGUAGGGAAAGUAAGUGACAAAAAGGUGAUUGAAGUGGGAAAAAAUGAUGACCUGGAGGACUCUAAGUCCUUAAGUGAUGAUACCGAUGUAGAGGUUACCUCUGAGGAUGAGUGGCAGUGUACUGAAUGCAAGAAAUUUAACUCUCCAAGCAAGAGGUACUGUUUUCGUUGUUGGGCCUUGAGGAAGGAUUGGUAUUCAGAUUGUUCAAAGUUAACCCAUUCUCUCUCCACGUCUGAUAUCACUGCCAUACCUGAAAAGGAAAAUGAAGGAAAUGAUGUCCCUGAUUGUCGAAGAACCAUUUCGGCUCCUGUCGUUAGACCUAAAGAUGCGUAUAUAAAGAAAGAAAACUCCAAACUUUUUGAUCCCUGCAACUCAGUGGAAUUCUUGGAUUUGGCUCACAGUUCUGAAAGCCAAGAGACCAUCUCAAGCAUGGGAGAACAGUUAGAUAACCUUUCUGAACAGAGAACAGAUACAGAAAACAUGGAGGAUUGCCAGAAUCUCUUGAAGCCAUGUAGCUUAUGUGAGAAAAGACCACGAGACGGGAACAUUAUUCAUGGAAGGACGGGCCAUCUUGUCACUUGUUUUCACUGUGCCAGAAGACUAAAGAAGGCUGGGGCUUCAUGCCCUAUUUGCAAGAAAGAGAUUCAGCUGGUUAUUAAGGUUUUUAUAGCAUAAUGGUAGUACGAACAUAAAAAUGCAUUUAUUCCGUUCACUUACCACAUUAUUUGAAAAUCAAUCCUUUAUUUAAUUUUAUUUCCAACCUGUCAGAGAAUGUUCUUAGGCAUCAAAAUCCAAGGUAGCUGUAAGAAAAAUACUGGAGCUAACAAUGAAGAACAGAAGUAAUCUGAUUAGUCAAAUUAUUAAGUGCCAUGGAUUACUUUAUGCAGCAGUCAGGUACAUAGUUAGGUGAACCCAAAAGAAAAACUCUUGAAAACAAGAGAUUUCUUCCAUGCACAUUUACAAUAUUGAGGUAUAAUUAACAUGAUAAAGUGUUUCCUUCUAACGAGUUGUAGAAAUCUGAGUAACCACCCAAAAAAGCAAUAGAAUGUUUCUGUCACCCCAAAACACUCCCUUCUGCCCCUCUUCAGACAGUCCUUCAGCUAUUUCAUGGCUCUCACCCUAGUUUUUUUUUUUUUUGCACUUUUUUUUUUCCGGGGGUAUAGGGGAGGUGUGGGGCGACAGGGUCUGUCUUGUUCUGUCUCCCAGGCUGAAGUGCAGUGCAGUGGUAUGAUCAUGGCUCACUGCAGCCUUGGUUUCCUGGGCAUAAGUGGUCUUCCCACUUCAGCCUCCUGAGUAGCUGAGACUAUAGACUAGCAUAACCACACUGGCUAAUUUUUUGUGGAGAUGAAGUCUCACUAUGUUGCCCAGGCUGGUCUCGAACUCCUGGGCUCAAACAAUCCUCCCGCCUCAGCCUUCCAAAUUGCUGGGAUUAUAGUCAUGAGGCACCUAGUCUGGCCCUUUUGCAAGACUUUAAUCUGAAAUCUAAAUUUUUAAAAUUUAAGUACUUACAAAGGAUAUACUAUCCAACAUAUUGCAUAUUAUAUAUGUGCUUUAAAGUUUUUUUUUUUUUUUGAGAGACGGUCUCACUUUGUCAUCCAAGCUGGAGUGCAGUGGUGCAAACACGGCCCACCUCCUGGGCUCAAGUGAUCCUCCAGCCUCAGCUUCCCUCACAGGCAUUCACUAUCACUCCCAGCUAAUUAAAAUAAUUUGUAGACGGUGUCUCGUUAUGUUGCCCAGGCUGGUCUCGAACUCCUGGGUUUAAGUGAUUCCCCCGCCUCAGCCUCCCAAAGUGUUGGGCUUACAGCCUUGAGCCACUAUGCUUGGCUCAAAGAUAUUUUUAUGAAAGCCCUGGGACUAUAGAUUUAGCUGAUUAAAUUUAUAGAAAAAGUCCUGUCAUAUAAACUGGCAAAGUCUGUUCUUAAUUUAAUUAGCCAAAUCAGACUUAACUUCCGUCAGAACAUGUCUUGGUUUUAAUUCAGAUAAACACACAAACAUACUUCUCUGGCACAGCCUUCAGAAGCAUCAGUUUUUGUUUUGUUUUGUUUUGUUUUUUGAGACAGGGUCUUGCUCUGUCGCCCAGGCUGGAGUGCACUGGCACAAUCACAGUUCACUGCAGCCUCGACCUCCCAGAUCCAAGCAAUCCUCCCACCUAAGCCUCCCAAGUAGCUGGGUCUAUAGGCGCGUGCCACCACCAUGCCCAGCUGAAUUUUGUAUUUUUUGUACAGACAGCAUUUUGCCAUGUUGCCCAGGCUGGUCCCAAACUUCUAGCCUCAAGCAACCCUCCUGCCUCAGCCUCUCAAAGUGCUAGGAUUGCAGUCCUGAGCUACUGCCCCCUACCCUCUUUGCGUCUUAGGAGUCAUUUAGAUUUUUUUUGAUCCUUUUGUUUAGUGCCUCUGGAGCUGCUUACACCAAGGCAAUACGCCUUGAUAUACUGGAUGGUUGAGAGGCAGCCUCUUUUUUUUUUUUUUUUUUUUUUUUUUUUUGGAGGAUAGGGAGUAUGGCUGUUGUGAAAAGGGAGGUAAAGAGAAAUGGUAGAUCUGAAGAGGCCUCAUCAGAGCACAUAUUUUAGGACAACACAUAUGGAAAUUGGACAUCUUUAAGUUGGUUUCCAUAGAGCUAUGCAUGUAUCCUUACCCCCAUGGGAAAAUGUUGGUGUGUUCUCAAGGGUAUGCAUGUGUCAUUUUGAAGACCAAGGCCCUAGAAUUGUCAAACUUAAGGAUCAUAAAAAUCAUGAGGGUUGCUUGUUAAAAAUGUCCAAACGUGCAGAGACUGAUCUUUGAGAUCUGGACCAGGAAUUUGCAUUUGAACAAGUGUUCCUGGAAUCUCUAUGCAAGUUUUAUACAGAACAUACUUUUGGAAUCCUUGCCCUAGACAGGGGUGUCCAAUCUUUUGGCUUCCCUGGUCCACAAUGGAAGAAGAAUUGUCUUGGACCACACAUAAAAUACACUAACACUAACAAUAGCUGAUGAGCUAAAAAAAAAAAAAAAAAAAAUCGUGGACCGGGCGUAGUGGCUCACGCCUGUAAUCCCAACACUUUGGGAGAUCACCUAGGUCGGGAGUUUGAGACCAGCCUGACCGACAUGGAGAAACCCCAUUUUUACUAAAAAUACAAAAAAUUAGCUGGGCAUGGUGGUGCAUGCCUGUAGUCCCAGCUACUCAGGAGGCUGAGGCAGGAGAAUCGCUUGAACCUGAGAGGGGGAGAUUGCGGUGAGCUGAGAUUGCGCCAUUGCACCCCAGCCUGGGCAACAAUAGCGAAACUGUCUCAGAAAAAAGAAAAAAAAAAUCGCAAAAAGAAAAAUCUCAUAAUGUCGUUGUUGGUUUUUUUUUUUUUUUUUGAGACAGUCUCACUCUGUUGCCCAGGCUGGAGUGCAAUGGCAUGAUCUCUGCUCACCGCAACCUCUGCCUCCCGGGUUCAGGUGAUUCUCCUGCCUCAGCCUCCCAGAUAGCUGGGACUACAGGCACAUACCACCAUGCCUGGCUAAUUUUUGUAUUUUUAGUAGAGAUGGGGGUUUCACUGUGUUGGCCAGGCUGGUCUCGAACUCCUGACCUCAUGAUCCACACACCUCGGCCUCCCAAAGUCCUGCGAUUACAGGCGUGAGCUACCGCACCCAGCCAAGUUGUAAUUUUUAAUAAAACUUAAGAAGUAAACAUUUUACUUAUGUUUAUAGGUAUUUGAUCCUAAAUUUGACACAUCAUUGCCCAUGAAAGAAUCCUCUUAGGCUGCUCAGCUUCACUCUUCCUGCUUGCCCACCGGGGUUUUUCACUGCUUCUGUUAGCACUAAGUACUUAGACGAUCCUAAGAUAUGUGCUUGAGCCGAAUUUCAUCUUUACUUGUAGGAAACUUUAAACUAUUUCUUUUCUUUUCUUUUUUUUUUUUUUUUACUUGAGAUGGAGUUUUGCUCUUGUCGCCCAGGCUGGAGUGCAGUGGAGUGAUCUCGGCUCACUGCAACCUCUGCCUCCCGGGUUCAAAUGAUUCUCCUGCCUCAGCCUCCCAAGUAGCUGGGAUUACAGGUGUGCACCACCAUGUCUGGCUAAUUUUGUAUUUUUAGUAGAGAUGGUUUCACCAUGUUGGUCAGGCUGGUCUCGAACUCCUGACCUCAGGUCAUCCACCCACCUCAGCCUCGCAAAGUGCUGAGAUUACAGGCAUGAGCCACAGCGCCCAGCUUAAACUAUUUUCUUGGUCUGUUUUUGAUUUUCUUUUUUCCUUGCCACUGCGGUACAGAUUUUUUUUACUCACUGCCACUAAACUAAAGCAAGGCAUAGUUUAUAUGUGAAGUGUUCAGAGUUUACUGCUAUAAGGAAACUUCCAAAUACUGACAUUUACCUUUUAGCUGUAGUUAUUGGGACCAUGUGCUCUGGUUUUCUGGAGACUGCCAAAUUGCUCCCAUUUUUCUGCAUCCCACCUGGUUUCUUUCUGCAUGUCCCCUUUCACUUUCAAACCUCUUCAUUUGGAUGUUAAAUUAUAUGGUCACCUAGUUAUAGGUAAGCCUUGUUCGAGUUGAUAUCUUGAUUGUGAGGAAGGAUCUGUGUCAUUGGAGCUUGUUUCUGCUGCAACGUGCUGUAGACUAUGAAUAAUGAAAUCACACCACAUUACCAUCAGAUUUCUUGUUUUAGUUGUCAAAUUAAUAUUUAUGAUUGUUAUCUUGGGCGAAAAGUUCAGAGCAGAGAUGACAAAUCAUUAGAACAACGAUGAAUUUCAGUAUUACGGCUAAAAAGUUCUUCUGUCUGAAUAUUAACUCACUCUCCUUCCAGUGUACUUCACAGUAAUUGGUAUGCUUUUUUAUUUAAUGCUUAAAUCAAACUUUAUAAAAAUCUUAGACCAGAUCUUUAAUAUGGUAUGCCAUUUCCCCAGUCUACCAAUGGAAUAGUAUGGGUUUCUAAUCCUAGGCUUGUACAAUGGAUUGGAGUUGAGCCAUGCCAGCCUCCACACUGCCACUAACUUCUGUAAUGUAAGAUUGAGUCACUGCCAAGCAUUUGAAAUAUGCAGUUGUGUUUUAAUUAUAAUUUAUGUAUAGUUAGAUGUAUGUAGUGCAUUGUGUGGUAUUAUUUGGUUUGUAAGAAUUUAUUUUUAAGGGUCAAGGUCAUUUGUAACAUUUUGUGUGUGUCAAUUCAAUGCAAUGUUGGCUGCCUUUUGAAGUCUUUGAUAUAUUGGUGAAUAUUCUUCUGAUCUAUAAUACAAAGCUAUGUAAUGUUACCUCUUGACUCGCUUUUGAAAGGAAGACAAUUGUUAACUAGAUAUUUGAGUUUUUUCCCCUCAGAAUUAUGUGAAUUUCUGAUAUAUGGCUUUAGAUACUGUGAAUCUGUUUUCCAUUUAGUCAGUUAUCUGCUUAAAUUGUUCAGAACUAUAUCCUAACGAGCAAUUAGUUCUGAUGGUUCUCCCAGUCAUGAGUGUGCAUGUGUGCAAGCAUGUUUUGAUCCUGAUGCUACCUUUGCUAAAAAUGGCCAUAGAUUAGGAACUAGCUAUGUUUUUAGAAUCAAAGAUGAACCGGUAAGCUGUCUCAUGUACCAAACGUGAAAUUUACAGUGUUUACAAAUGUCUGGAAUUUUGCACUGCCAUAGGGAAUGUUAAGGUUACUUGGCUGGAAUUUAUCAGACUUGUGAGUAAACAAGUUGAAGUUUAGCAGAUGAGGGGGAAUAUUGAGGCCCCUAAGGCUAAACAAAAUAAUCAGUAUCUGAGAUAGUGGCUAAUGUGGCUCCCCAGGCCUAAUUUGGGAACAGUUUUUCCUGAUUGCUUUGAGAAGUACUUUCUUUUGACAGAAAUUUUCAUUCUGCUUGCCAUUGCUAUAUUCUCCCUUUAUAGGAGCCAUUGGAUUUCUUUCCUUUUGUGGGAAAUGUCCCAUUAGCAUUUUCAGAUCUUUUGAUGUGCACUAAUGCCAUUAUUGGUAAUGCCGUUAUUGGUGAAUACAGCAUAGUUAAAUAAACUGUUACAGUAAAUCUACACUUGGAUUUGCUGCACCUCUACCAAUAGCCUUUUGAAUGACUGAAAGUGUUAACAGAGAAAGAGGCAUGUCUGCAGAAAGAGAUAGCUAAUAUUUUUUGGUACUUUAUCUGAAAUCCAAGAUGCUGCUUCCCCUGCAGGUUGUUUUCCUUCUUACGAUCCUCAUUGAAUCCCCUCUGGGAGCACAGGACAGUUAGUAGAACUCUCCAUUUCUUUUUUUUUUUUUUUAGACGGAGUCUCUCUCUGUCGCCCCGGCUGGAGUGCAGUGGCGCGAUCUCGGCUCACUGCAACCUCCGCCUCCCGGGUUCACCCCAUUCUCCUGCCUCAGCCUCCCUAGUAGCUGGGACUAUAGGCGCCCGCCACCACGCCUGGCUAAUUUUUGUAUUUUUAUUGGAGACGGGGUUUCACCGUCUUAGCCAGGAUGGUCUUGAUCUCCUGACCUCGUGAUCUGCCCACCUCAGCCUCCCAAAGUACUGGGAUUACAGGCGUGAGCCACCGCGCCCGGCCGGAACUCUCCAUUUCUUAAGGUAAAGAGGGUCAAGGAUACCUAAAAAGGGUCAAAUAAUGCUAGAAGAGCAAUUCCUCUUUCAGAGCAGUUGCUGUAAUUUGGCAAAUGCUUUAUCGAAGAUUGAUAUUAGGCUAGGGGCGGUGGCUUACGCCUGUAAUCCCAGCACUUUGGGAGGCCGAGGUGGGUGGAUUGCCUGAGCUCAGGAGUUCGAGACCAGUCUGACCAGUAUGGUGAAACCCUGUCUCUACUAAAAAUACAAAAAUUAGCCGGUCGUGGUGGCGUGCACCUGUAGUCCCAGCUACUUGGCAGGUUGAGACAGGAGAAUCGCUUGAACCUGGGAGGUGGAGGUUGCAGUGAGCCGAGACUGCACCACUGCGCUCCCACCUGGGUGACAGAGACUCUGUCUCAAAAAAAAGGACAUUUAUCAUUAUAACAUCUUAUUAGAGCCCCUAAUUUCUUAUCUGAAGGCACUGUUUUUUUUUUUAAACAGUUAAGUACUGAUGUCAACAGACAAAUAUUUCUGAUCAGAUAGUCCCCUGUCAACAGUAGCAAAUGUGGUUUCAUAAAGUGGGAAGAAAACAGCAUUUUAAAGUAACUUUUUGGGAGACUGAUUUGAGUAAUAAUAAAACUCUGGUCUCCCUUAAGAAAAAAAAACCCUUCCACCUUUACUGUGUCAUUUAUAUCCCCUUAGUUCCAAAGUUAAUUAUCUUAUUUCUGGAUAUUGCUUUUAUACCAAAGACCCUUAUCAGCCCUUGUAACUACAGUAUCUUUAGAUAAGAUUCCUCUUUCCAGUCAGUCCUGGGAAAUGUUUCUGUUGCAGAGUUAGGCGGUAGAUGGGAAGCUGUGAUGGCAGAGCUACUAUCUAAUAAAGUAACAACUCGUAGUUGAGGCUUCCUUUCUGUGUGUGAUGGGGGAUAGGGAGUUAGCUCCCCUGUUGUCUCAGCACUAAGAAAUUGAGGUCAGGCCAGGCGCGGUGGUUCACUCCUGUUAUUCCAGCACUGGGGUGGCCAAAGUGGGCAGAUUGCUUGCGCUCUGGAGCUCGAGACCAGCCUGGGCAACAUGGUGAAACCCUGUCUCUACCAAAAAUACAAAAAAAAAGCUGGGCAUGGUGGGUGCAUGCUUGUCCCAGCUACUGAGGAGGCUGAGGUGGGAGGAUCGCUUGAGCCUGGGAGGUGGAGGUUGCAGUGAGCUGAGAUGGCACCACUGCAAUCCAAGGUGGGUGACAGAGACGCUGUCUCAAAGAAAUUGAGGUCAGGCUUCCUUCUUACAGAAUUAUUUUUUUCUCUGUAGUUUGCCUCAUUUUUUCACUUUCUUUUCAAUGAGAAUCGAAGUGUUUCUUUUGGGUUUUUUUUUCCCCCUUUUAAAAUCAACAGGAAAUGUUUCAAAGGAGGGAUGAAAUGCUUCUUGGCUUCCUCAGCACUUGGCAAGGUAGACCUCAUAGCAACCUUGAAUAUGACUUUCUUUAGUCUCUAGCUAUGCACUAUUAAGUGCCUCUUGGGUAGAGGUAGAGUUAAGUAUUGAGUGCCAGUCUUGACGUCCGUAUGCCUCAGUUUUUCUCAUAUAUAAAAAGCAGUAUACAUACCUACCCUUUUCUACCUCAUCAUUUGUUGUAGGGAUUAAAUCCGGGAGAGCAAUUCUGAAGCCUAUAAAUUUCCUUGAAGAGAUCUAAGAACCUAUUAUGCUCUUGGUGUACCAAGCUCUGGGGUAUAUAUUCAGAAUACCUCAUGUUCUGGAAGCUGAGCACUAGCUCCCCUUUAUUGCCUGCCUGGCAGAGCCUGUUUGAUUACUGCAGGCCCUUUUACCCAUGCUUCUAGUUUAGGUAUUCUUUCUUUGAUAUGAGGCUCUUGACCAGAAAAGAGUUCUUUCUCUAGGUGUUCUGAGAGAAGUUUGUAAAUUUGGAUAGUACAUUCUAUCCUGAUAAAACCACCUUGCUGUGGUCUUGAUGUACAAAAAAAAAUUUUUUUUUUGAGACAGAGUCUUACUCUGUCACCCAGGCUGGAAUGCAGUGGCGCAAUCUUGGUUCACUGCAACCCCCGCCUCCUGGGUUCAAGCGAUCCUCCUGCCUCAACCUCUCAAGUAGCUGGGACUACAGGCGUGCACCACCACACCUGGCUAAUUUUGUAUUUUUAGUAGAGACAGGGUUUCACCAUGUUGGCCAGGCUGGUCUUGAACUCCUGACCUCAGGCGAUCUGCCCGCCUUGGCCUCCCAAAGUACUGGGAUUACAGGCGUGAGCAACUGCUCCUGGCCCAAAACAUCUCUUUCUACAUACACUUGAGUAGGUGGCAUAAAAUGCACUGUCAAUAUAUAGAAAACAUGAAAUUUUCCAAAUAUUUCCGAUCAGAGAAUCACAAGAGCAGCAAAUGUGGUUUCAUCAAGUGGGAAGAAAGCAGCAAUUUAAAAUAACUUUUUGGGAGACUGAAUUGAGUAAUAAUAAAACUUCAGUCUUUCGCUAAUAAUAAUAAUAAUAAUAAUAAUAACAACAACUUAUUGAAUGUGGCCAGCUCACUAGAUGAGGAAAGAGGAAGGCAUUUUCUGCAUUCUUGCCUAGUUUUCCUUAUAAGCACCACUAAGUUAAUAGCUCUGUCUUUUUGGUGUUUGCACUAUGUAAUGCUUUUAAUACUUUUUAAUUGUGCUUUUUUAUGUAUUAAAUGUUUUUCCUUUUGCCA